GUAGUCCUGGCGGGCGUGGGCCCUUGAGGUGUGCUGGGAGCUGUGGUCCGGGUCGGCGGGCGCGCAAGUUGGCUAGUCUCUGCGGCCACCUCCGGAAGGGUCCGCCGGCUGUGCUGGUGAGGUGGGUUUCGGGGGUGUUCUCCGUCCUGAUCCAGGCUGGAGAGGGGCACAGCAGGUCCAGAAGCCGCGAACCUCUGGGGCGGCCAGAGCGAGAUGCGGGGUACCGCCCAGCGGGUAGAGAGUGAGAGGCUGACUAGGGGACGUGAGUAGACGGACUGCGAGUGCCGGACACACGCGCAGAGGAUGUGACGGACUGACGGACCAGGCGUGGACGGACCGUGUGUGCACGGACUGACGGACCCGGUGUGGACAGACUCACGGACCGAAUGUGGUGCGGAAUGACACACUGAGUGCCGGACGGACCGACGGAGAAUGUGUCGGACUGACGGAGUGUGUGUCGGAUGGACUGAUUGACCGGGUGUGGGGCGGACGAAGUGUGGAGCGGGCGGACAGAUAACAGAUAAAAUGUAGGACCAGUGGCCUGGGAGGGUGUGGGGCGGACCCGUUUAUGUGUCUGAUAGGCGGUUCUGUGUCUGACACCUCUUGGGUGUGUGUAUCUGACGGGUUGGAGUGUGUGAUUCUGAUAGGUUGAGUGUAACACUAACCAUGGAGUGUGUGACUGACAGAGAUGGUUGCCGUUUGAGACUUCCUACGUGGGUUGUGAGAUACUGUGAGAGGGUGAGCGUGUGACGGUGGGAUUUCAAGUGUGACUGAUUUUCUUUGUGUGUCCUUGAGAUGGUGACUAAGAUUAUGAAUGACUGUGAUCAGAAUAAUACUGUGUGAUGGAAAUGCUGCGAGGGCCUGUGUUUAUUUUUGAGACGGAGUCUUGCUCUGUUGCCCAGGCUGGAGUGCAGUGGCGCAAUCUCGGCUCACUGCAACCUCCAUCUCCCGGGUUCAAGCGAUUAUCCUGCGUCAGCCUCCCGAGUAGCUGGGAUUACAGGCACCGGCCACCACACUUGGCUAAUUUUUGUAUUUUUGGUAGAGACGGGCUUUCACCAUGUUGGUUAGGCUGGCCCGGAACUCCUGACCUCAGGUGAUCCACCUGCCUAGGCCUCCCAAAGUGCUGGGAUUAUAGGCAUGAGCCACCAUGCCUGGCCAGGCCUGUGUUUAUUUGACUGAUUAUAGGUGACAUUGAGAUAUUUCCUGUGUCUGGGUAUUUUGAAGGCUGUGGCUGACAGACUGUACCUGAGAUAAUAUGUGUUAAUAUCUGAUUGACUGAGAUUUUUAUCAGGGAGACUAAAACUUGGGUGAUCCACAAACAGUUUACCAAGCAUAUGAGAGAGGAUUUGUGCUUUGCCAUGUCUGCAGCUGAAACUGAGUGACUAGUGGUCAUUCAGCUGGGCUUAUGGAUAUGUCCCCCAGUGUUUGCUUACGUGUAGCAGGGGGCUAUGGUAUCCAUACAUCUACUGCAUGUUUACUGUGCACCAGGCCUGUGCUGGACACUUAUAAUAAAUCACCUCACAUAAUCUCAUAGCAACCCUCUGAGGCCCAGUUCCAAGGCUCCGGCAUCCUGUGUCUCACUGAGCACUGCUGCCCGAUGGCCAUCCCCAAGCACUCCCUGAGCCCAGUGCCGUGGGAAGAGGACAGCUUCCUUCAAGUGAAGGUGGAGGAGGAAGAGGAAGCCAGCCUCUCCCAGGGCGGAGAAUCCAGCCAUGACCACAUUGCUCACUCUGAGGCUGCACGCCUGCGCUUCCGGCACUUCCGCUAUGAGGAGGCAUCUGGUCCACACGAGGCCCUGGCCCACCUCCGAGCGCUGUGCUGUCAGUGGCUGCAGCCCGAGGCGCACUCCAAGGAGCAGAUACUGGAGCUGCUGGUGCUGGAGCAGUUCCUGGGUGCGCUGCCCCCAGAGAUCCAAGCCUGGGUGGGAGCCCAGAGUCCCAAGAGCGGAGAGGAAGCCGCUGUGCUGGUGGAGGAUCUGACUCAGGUGCUGGACAAGAGAGGAUGGGAUCCAGGAGCCGAGCCCACAGAGGCAAGCUGCAAGCAGAGUGACCUGGGAGAGUCAGAGCCAUCAAAUGUCACUGAGACCCUCAUGGGAGGUGUUUCCCUUGGACCCGCCUUUGUCAAGGCAUGUGAACCUGAGGGCAGCUCAGAGAGGUCUGGACUAUCAGGGGAGAUCUGGACAAAGUCUGUCACCCAACAGAUCCACUUCAAGAAAACUUCAGGGCCUUACAAGGAUGUCCCCACAGACCAGCGUGGCCGUGAAUCUGGUGCCUCGAGGAACAGUUCUAGUGCGUGGCCAAACCUCACCUCCCAAGAGAAGCCUCCUUCAGAAGACAAAUUUGAUCUGGUGGAUGCUUAUGGGACAGAGCCUCCAUACACCUACUCAGGGAAGAGGUCCUCCAAGUGUCGCGAGUGUAGGAAGAUGUUCCAGAGUGCUUCGGCGCUCGAGGCACACCAGAAGACCCAUUCUCGGAAGACCCCAUAUGCCUGCAGCGAGUGUGGGAAAGCCUUCAGCCGGAGCACUCACCUCGCCCAGCACCAGGUUGUCCACACAGGGGCGAAGCCCCAUGAGUGUAAGGAAUGUGGGAAGGCCUUCAGCCGAGUCACCCACCUGACUCAGCACCAAAGGAUUCAUACUGGAGAGAAACCCUACAAAUGUGGGGAAUGUGGUAAAACCUUCAGCCGCAGCACUCACCUCACCCAGCACCAGCGGGUGCACACGGGGGAGCGGCCCUACGAGUGUGACGCGUGUGGGAAAGCCUUCAGCCAGAGCACGCACCUGACUCAACACCAGCGCAUCCACACCGGGGAGAAGCCCUACAAGUGUGACGCGUGUGGCCGAGCCUUCAGCGACUGCUCAGCCCUGAUCCGACAUCUGAGAAUCCACUCUGGAGAGAAGCCAUAUCAGUGUAAGGUUUGUCCGAAGGCCUUUGCACAGAGCUCCUCCCUCAUUGAGCACCAGAGGAUCCACACGGGAGAGAAGCCUUAUAAGUGCAGCGACUGUGGGAAGGCCUUCAGUCGUAGCUCAGCCCUGAUGGUUCACUUGCGGAUCCACAUCACGGUGCUGCAAUGACCGGAAGUCGCCCCUGGGGGCGUAGCACAGCGUCUUCUCGGAGGCUCGAGGUCUAAGAGAAACGCUGAGUUCCUGAAGAGCCACAGACAGGGUGGGUGAUUGAUGAGUUGUCAAAAUGAUAGGUGCCUGAGGGCAGACUCGGGCUGUCUAGGAACCACUCUGCAUUUGAGGAACCCUGAUGAGCACAAGGUGAUUCAGGCCAGCUGGAGAAGCUUCCAGAAGGGCCCUGCACUGCUACCCUCUAUUUCCCACUCAGGGCUGUCCCAGAGAGAAGGCAGCCGAACUGAGGAUUUAGACUGGUUCUGAGGGCCAGGGCAAAUGAAGGCGCAUGUCUCUCAGAACUCAGCGUCCCAAGACGCUCUGGGCGGGCCAACUGUAGCUUGUUCUCAUGUGGUUCUUCUUGCCUGCUUUUCUGCUGCUUAGCCCAGAACGGACACCUGCCAUGCCCACCUCUGUGCCUUGGCACCUACUAUUUCCACUCCAGACUAUUUUGUGCCUAACUGCAAGGCUGACUUUUGAGACUGCCUCUUCCACGAUGCCUUUUCUACACUCUGCCUCUCUCAUGGUUUCCUGUCGUAAUCAGUGGUGCUGCUUGACACCUGCCCAGCAUGUUCCUGUCUCUCCUUUUCCUUCCACAUCCCACCAGUCACCAGCGCUAUUGUUUUAACCUAAAGCUUAUCUGUAAUUCACCUCCUUUUCCACCACUGCUACCUUAUGUGAGCCCUCAUUGCCUCUUGCCUGGAUUAUAGCCGGGGUCUCCUUCCUGACCACUUCCUGCCUUUAUUCUCUGCCCCUGUAUCACUCUCCAGGGGACUCUUGAUAUUACUUAGAUCUGACUGUGUCACUCCAAGGUGGAAAGCUCUCCAACCCAUCUUCUACAGCACAGCUUCCUGAACAGGGUAUAAGUAUGCUGAGAUGCAGGCUGCUCUGGGCCCCGAGCAACCUCUCCAGUUAUCCUCAUAUGCAUGUAUGAAUACUGUCAUUUUUCUGUGCGUGCAGUGAAAAUGGCCUCAUCUCAUACCAUGGCUCCACCUUCCAUACACCAGCCACACGGAACUACUGUGGUCCCUGAAGGAGCCAUACAUUUUCCCACUUAUGUGCCUUUGUACCUGUGCCUGGAACCCUCCUCUUCUUUUUCUUUUUCUUUUCUUUUCUUUUUUUUUUUUUGAGAUGGAGUCUCGCUCUGUCGCCCAGGCUGGAGUGCAGUGGCGCGAUCUCGGCUCACUGCAAGCUCUGCCUCCCGGGUUCAUGCCAUUCUCCUGCCUCAGCCUCCCAAGUAGCUGGGACUACAGGCGCCUGCCACCACGCCCAGCUAGUUUUUUUUUUUUUUUGUAUUUUUAGUAGAGAUGGAGUUUCACCAUGUUAGCCAGGAUGGUCUCGAUCUCCUGACCUCGUGAUCCACCCGCCUCGGCCUCCCAAAGUGCUGGGAUUACAGGCGUGAGCCACCGCACCUGGCCCUCCUUUUUCAUCUAAGGUGUUUCAAAUGUUGCCCAAAGAAACCUCCCUGCUCUCCGGGAGCAGACUUCAGCUUGCCCUCUCUGCUUCCAGAGCACCUCCUAGAUACCUCUCUUACAACUCCUGCCACCUUGUUUUACUUAUUUGCUCCUUGUAGAGCUGCCUUUUCCAAGGAUACCAUAAACUCCUGAGAGCAGGGGCCAUGUCUUACUCUCAGUAUCUACAACACACAAGACUCAGUAGGCCCUGACUGAUGUCUCUUACAUGAAUGUGACUGGUGCCCCCAGGAGGCAGUCACCGUGCUGUCUCUGCCCCACAUUGUCCUUAUGUAUGUUUACAUGGAUGUCUCCCCAGCAGCUUGAACCCUGGAGAGCAAGAAUAAUCUGAUUUUCCUGGGGGCCAGCACCCAAAUAAGCCUGGCAUGCAGUGGCCUCAAUAAAAUGUGACUGUAUUGAGUCAUUUUCUAGGGCCCCAGAUCCCCUGGUGUCAUGGACUUAGUCUUUGCCAGCAUUCUGUCCAUGUGUUCUCUGGUCUUCUCUCACAAUGCUGCAUCCCUGUCCCAUUUUUAGGGUCCCUGUCUAUCACUGGAUGCUGCAGCUUCUGUUCAUUACUGUUAGUGUAUCAUUCUUCAUGCCUCUGUUUCUGUGAUGGUCUCAUCAUAUGUGAACCAUUUGACCUGGCGUAUUGUGUACUAGUCACCGUCACCAUCUCUCCAUAUGUAUCUCCCUGUAUUUCGGGCCCAUUCCCUCUAUGUCAAGAGUAAAUAGAGGCACAGAGACUGAUGAGAAACGUUCAUAACAUGAAGGUAAGACUCAGGGAGACAGAGACUUUGUGGAAGUAUCUCUGAGGGAGUCCCAGACACAGGCAGAGAGGGCCACAUAUCGUGUGCCAGAGGCUGAGAGACUGAGAGGGAUGACAGGCUUAGGGGAAAACUCAGAGAGGAGAGAUGCACAUUCCUAGUGAAAUUGCACAGGCUUCCAGCAUGCUGGAGGGAACAGAAAAGGCAUGGGCCUGAAUUCAGGCUGCAGAGCCUGACUCCUCCCUGUGGCUACUUUUGGGACCUAAGAUAAGUGACUUUCCUGAACCUCCAUGACCUCCUCAUAUGUAAACCAGGGACAGGACCCACCUUGUGUAGUGCCUGACCCAAAGCCUGGCCCUGCACACUGUCUCUGACUCACAGCAAUCAUCAGCACCUCUCUUUGCCUCCUACUUGCUCAGUCUCUGUCACAAGAACUGGAUCUCCAUCCCCUUGAUGCUCUGAGCAUCUUCACCCAUUUGGUCGUUGAGACAUAUCUGUCCAUGUCUGUCUAAAAGGGGAGGAGAUGAGGGAGAAAAAAGGGAAUCUACUCAGAGCCUGUGUGUGCUGCCCAGUCUACCAAAUAAUUUAUAUACAUCUCAGUCCUCACACAACCAUCCCUGUUUUAUAGAGGAGGAAGUGGCUUAGAGAAUGUAACUGACCAAAGUCACACUGCCAGGAACUGGAAGCACUAGGAUUUGACAGCAUAUCCAAAUAUGUCAGCAAUUUCAAUAAACAUGACUGUACUCAACAAA